GAAACCUAACCCGCCCUGGGGAGGCGCGCAGCAGAGGCUCCGAUUCGGGGCAGGUGAGAGGCUGACUUUCUCUCGGUGCGUCCAGUGGAGCUCUGAGUUUCGAAUCGGCGGCGGCGGAUUCCCCGCGCGCCCGGCGUCGGGGCUUCCAGGAGGAUGCGGAGCCCCAGCGCGGCGUGGCUGCUGGGGGCCGCCAUCCUGCUAGCAGCCUCUCUCUCCUGCAGUGGCACCAUCCAAGGAACCAGUAGAUCCUCUAAAGGAAGAAGCCUUAUUGGUAAGGUUGAUGGCACAUCCCACGUCACUGGAAAAGGAGUUACAGUUGAAACAGUCUUUUCUGUGGAUGAGUUUUCUGCAUCUGUCCUCACUGGAAAACUGACCACUGUCUUCCUUCCAAUUGUCUACACAAUUGUGUUUGUGGUGGGUUUGCCAAGUAACGGCAUGGCCCUGUGGGUCUUUCUUUUCCGAACUAAGAAGAAGCACCCUGCUGUGAUUUACAUGGCCAAUCUGGCCUUGGCUGACCUCCUCUCUGUCAUCUGGUUCCCCUUGAAGAUUGCCUAUCACAUACAUGGCAACAACUGGAUUUAUGGGGAAGCUCUUUGUAAUGUGCUUAUUGGCUUUUUCUAUGGCAACAUGUACUGUUCCAUUCUCUUCAUGACCUGCCUCAGUGUGCAGAGGUAUUGGGUCAUCGUGAACCCCAUGGGGCACUCCAGGAAGAAGGCAAACAUUGCCAUUGGCAUCUCCCUGGCAAUAUGGCUGCUGAUUCUGCUGGUCACCAUUCCUUUGUAUGUCGUGAAGCAGACCAUCUUCAUUCCUGCCCUGAACAUCACGACCUGUCAUGAUGUUUUGCCUGAGCAGCUCUUGGUGGGAGACAUGUUCAAUUACUUCCUCUCUCUGGCCAUUGGGGUCUUUCUGUUCCCAGCCUUCCUCACAGCCUCUGCCUAUGUGCUGAUGAUCAGAAUGCUGCGAUCUUCUGCCAUGGAUGAAAACUCAGAGAAGAAAAGGAAGAGGGCCAUCAAACUCAUUGUCACUGUCCUGGCCAUGUACCUGAUCUGCUUCACUCCUAGUAACCUUCUGCUUGUGGUGCAUUAUUUUCUGAUUAAGAGCCAGGGCCAGAGCCAUGUCUAUGCCCUGUACAUUGUAGCCCUCUGCCUCUCUACCCUUAACAGCUGCAUCGACCCCUUUGUCUAUUACUUUGUUUCACAUGAUUUCAGGGAUCAUGCAAAGAACGCUCUCCUUUGCCGAAGUGUCCGCACUGUAAAGCAGAUGCAAGUAUCCCUCACCUCAAAGAAACACUCCAGGAAAUCCAGCUCUUACUCUUCAAGUUCAACCACUGUUAAGACCUCCUAUUGAGUUUUCCAGGUCCUCAGAUGGGAAUUGCACAGUAGGAUGUGGAACCUGUUUAAUGUUAUGAGGACGUGUCUGUUAUUUCCUAAUCAAAAAGGUCUCACCACAUACCAUGUGGAUGCAGCACCUCUCAGGAUUGCUAGGAGCUCCCCUGUUUGCAUGAGAAAAGUAGUCCCCCAAAUUAACAUCAGUGUCUGUUUCAGAAUCUCUCUACUCAGAUGACCCCAGAAACUGAACCAACAGAAGCAGACUUUUCAGAAGAUGGUGAAGACAGAAACCCAGUAACUUGCAAAAAGUAGACUUGGUGUGAAGACUCACUUCUCAGCUGAAAUUAUAUAUAUACACAUAUAUAUAUUUUACAUCUGGGAUCAUGAUAGACUUGUUAGGGCUUCAAGGCCCUCAGAGAUGAUCAGUCCAACUGAACGACCUUACAAAUGAGGAAACCAAGAUAAAUGAGCUGCCAGAAUCAGGUUUCCAAUCAACAGCAGUGAGUUGGGAUUGGACAGUAGAAUUUCAAUGUCCAGUGAGUGAGGUUCUUGUACCACUUCAUCAAAAUCAUGGAUCUUGGCUGGGUGCGGUGCCUCAUGCCUGUAAUCCUAGCACUUUGGGAGGCUGAGGCAGGCAAUCACUUGAGGUCAGGAGUUCGAGACCAGCCUGGCCAUCAUGGCGAAACCUCAUCUCUACUAAAAAUACAAAAGUUAACCAGGUGUGUGGUGCACGUUUGUAAUCCCAGUUACUCAGGAGGCUGAGGCACAAGAAUUGAGUAUCACUUUAACUCAGGAGGCAGAGGUUGCAGUGAGCCGAGAUUGCACCACUGCACUCCAGCUUGGGUGAUAAAAUAAAAUAAAAUAGUCGUGAAUCUUGUUCAAAAUGCAGAUUCCUCAGAUUCAAUAAUGAGAGCUCAGACUGGGAACAGGGCCCAGGAAUCUGUGUGGUACAAACCUGCAUGGUGUUUAUGCACACAGAGAUUUGAGAACCAUUGUUCUGAAUGCUGCUUCCAUUUGACAAAGUGCCGUGAUAAUUUUUGAAAAGAGAAGCAAACAAUGGUGUCUCUUUUAUGUUCAGCUUAUAAUGAAAUCUGUUUGUUGACUUAUUAGGACUUUGAAUUAUUUCUUUAUUAACCCUCUGAGUUUUUGUAUGUAUUAUUAUUAAAGAAAAAUGCAAUCAGGAUUUUAAACAUGUAAAUACAAAUUUUGUAUAACUUUUGAUGACUUCAGUGAAAUUUUCAGGUAGUCUGAGUAAUAGAUUGUUUUGCCACUUAGAAUAGCAUUUGCCACUUAGUAUUUUAAAAAAUAAUUGUUGGAGUAUUUAUUGUCAGUUUUGUUCACUUGUUAUCUAAUACAAAAUUAUAAAGCCUUCAGAGGGUUUGGACCACAUCUCUUUGGAAAAUAGUUUGCAACAUAUUUAAGAGAUACUUGAUGCCAAAAUGACUUUAUACAACGAUUGUAUUUGUGACUUUUAAAAAUAAUUAUUUUAUUGUGUAAUUGAUUUAUAAAUAACAAAAUUUUUUUUACAACUUA